ACUUCCUUCCUCGGCCGGGAUGGGCGGCGCGGGACUGAGUGAUCGGCCUUGCGUCCGGCGGGUAAUCCCCAUCUGAUCUGCUGCCUGUGAGCUGCUGACUGCCGGGGCGCGCGAGCCUAGGGGGCACGGGCAGCAGCGCGGCGAUGACCUGAUCCCGAGCCCGCCAGGGCGCCCCUUCCUUCCCUCCCUUCCCUCGCUCCCUCUGAGCCUGUGCGGAGACCAGCUCGGUGCGGCGGCCCCGGGUGGACCAUGGCGGGGAGCUCCAGUUAAAGGCGUGUGGGCGCCGAGCUGGAGAGGACACCUUCGGCAUCGCUGCCUUUUGAGGGGGCUUAUUUAAACUACUGAGUCAUUCCAGAUUUAGGAUUCCCUAAAUAAUCACCAACUGUGCCCGUCUCGUGCCGGAAAGCAAGCGGAAAGAGAAAGAGCGCCCACUCUUGGGACCCCGCAGAUCGCCUCUCGCUGGUUUCUCCCCGAGGGGUGCUUGGCCCUCGAGGAUCUCCCUCCCUCCCUCGCGCCCUCCCCCCUCCCUCGCCUCCCGCUCUCUUUGCAGUGCUGCUGGCCGGGAGUUGCUCUCACCGCAGCUGGAAACAGCUGCCCCCGCCCCGCGCCCCUACCCAGACUCCGGGUAACCGCUCCCACUUCGCGCCUCUCGGAAUUCCAGAACUCGGGUGGCCGGCCCCUGGAAAGCCGCAGCCGGCGCGAUGCAUUCUGUAGACCUCACCCUGCUGGGACGGACCUCCUAAUCUUCAGAACCGCGGGCCGCAGGGAGUUAAAUUGCUGCCUUCCUCUCCUUCUCUCGUGCGGUUGGUGGCUUGUUUUCUAAAGGAACGUUUUAUUCACUUUUUAGUAUUUUCUACCGGGGGCGCGCUACCCGCCUGGGUCCAGACUCUGCUUUGUAAACGGGUUUUCUAUGUAUGUAUGUGUAGGUAUACUUUGGACACCUUACAACGCUUGCGCCUCUCCAACAGAGGCACGUCUUGUUAUUUUGGGCAUCGUUCUUCCCCUUCCACUUGGUACCCCGAACGCAGUGUGACUAAACUCCCCACUGCCCCUUGGACGCCGAUCGCCUUGGGGUGCAAGUUUGGGGUGCAAACGUCUACUUCGCAAGAGGGCCUGGGACCGCCCCGCCCCGCCCCCCGGCCGCCAGAGGUUGGGGAAGUUUACAUCUGGAUUUUCACACAUUUUGUCGCCACUGCCCAGACUUUGACUAACCUUGUGAGCGCCGGGUUUUCGAUACUGCAGCCUCCUCAAAUUUUAGCACUGCCUCCCCGCGACUGCCCUUUCCCUGGCCGCCCAGGUCCUGCCCUCGCCCCGGCGGAGCGCAAGCCGGAGGGCGCAGUAGAGGCUGGGGCCUGAGGCCCUCGCUGAGCAGCUAUGGCUGCGGCGAUAGCCAGCUCCUUGAUCCGGCAGAAGCGGCAGGCGAGGGAGUCCAACAGCGACCGAGUGUCGGCCUCCAAGCGCCGCUCCAGCCCCAGCAAAGACGGGCGCUCCCUGUGCGAGAGGCACGUCCUCGGGGUGUUCAGCAAAGUGCGCUUCUGCAGCGGCCGCAAGAGGCCGGUGAGGCGGAGACCAGAACCCCAGCUCAAAGGGAUUGUGACAAGGUUAUUCAGCCAGCAGGGAUACUUCCUGCAGAUGCACCCAGAUGGUACCAUUGAUGGGACCAAGGACGAAAACAGCGACUACACUCUCUUCAAUCUAAUUCCCGUGGGCCUGCGUGUAGUGGCCAUCCAAGGAGUGAAGGCUAGCCUCUAUGUGGCCAUGAAUGGUGAAGGCUAUCUCUACAGUUCAGAUGUUUUCACUCCAGAAUGCAAAUUCAAGGAAUCUGUGUUUGAAAACUACUAUGUGAUCUAUUCUUCCACACUGUACCGCCAGCAAGAAUCAGGCCGAGCUUGGUUUCUGGGACUCAAUAAAGAAGGUCAAAUUAUGAAGGGGAACAGAGUGAAGAAAACCAAGCCCUCAUCACAUUUUGUACCGAAACCUAUUGAAGUGUGUAUGUACAGAGAACCAUCGCUACAUGAAAUUGGAGAAAAACAAGGGCGUUCAAGGAAAAGUUCUGGAACACCAACCAUGAAUGGAGGCAAAGUUGUGAAUCAAGAUUCAACAUAGCUGAGAACUCUCCCCUUCUUCCCUCUCUCAUCCCUUCCCCUUCCCUUCCUUCCCAUUUACCCAUUUCCUUCCAGUAAAUCCACCCAAGGAGAGGAAAAUAAAAUGACAACGCAAGACCUAGUGGCUAAGAUUCUGCACUCAAAAUCUUCCUUUGUGUAGGACAAGAAAAUUGAACCAAAGCUUGCUUGUUGCAAUGUGGUAGAAAAUUCACGUGCACAAAGAUUAGCACACUUAAAAGCAAAGGAAAAAAUAAAUCAGAACUCCAUAAAUAUUAAAUUAAACUGUAUUGUUAUUAGUAGAAGGCUAAUUGUAAUGAAGACAUUAAUAAAGAUGAAAUAAACUUAUUACUUUAAAGGAAAGGAUUUGGAGAAUUGAACUCACAAACUGAUGUUAUAUACUCAAUAGCUUAAACUCAUGAUAAUGCUGCGAUGUGUGGUUUUGCUUGAUUUUGUAUUUUAUUUGGGCAUCUGGAAUUGACACACCAUUACAUUCUGUUUGCAGGAUUUUUUUUGUAACCAUGAAAUUGAACAUUUCCAAAUUAUAAACUAUGUUAAUACCUAUAAAAUAUAUAGCCAGGAACCAUUUAUCAUCAAGAAAAGUGUAAGAAAUUAUUUUUGAGAUGUAAUUUAAGAUUGUUUUAUGUAAAAGGAAAAUCUUGUAUGGCAUCGAAUAGCCUUAAUGAGUUUAAUUCUUUCACAAAAAUGAUUUCAAAUUAUCCUAGAGUAUAACAUUUUUAUCAAAGAUAUUAUUUCCGGAGUUCUUCUUUCUUUCUUUUUUUUUUUUUUUUAGUAAUUUAGCAAAAACAUUACUGUUCUAAUGCUGAAGUGACUUUUGCCAGUGCCAUGUCCAGGUGGUGAGGUAUAAGUUACUUGCUCUUAGCAUUUGGUCUGAUUUUUUUGCUUUGUGGACACCUUUGAGAGUAUCCACAAAGCAAUGUCUCAGGUGUGGACACCUGAGAGCAUGUUUUAGAAAGCUUUGUACCCUGUCUUGUGGCAGGAAAGAAAGAACAGGGGUUUUACAUAAGGAAAUAAGUCCUAGGAAAUUAGUCAACGCAAAUUGCAUUUGCGUUUGUACCUUACCACAGUCUUAUAUUGUUUUUUAAACUCUGCCAUGAAAUUUGGAGACAUGACUGUGAAAUUCCUAACUUACUAUCUUACAAAGCCAGUAGCUAAUUUGUUGCUCUAUGUAUGAUCCUGUUACAAGUCCAGUUUGCAAUUCAUUUGUUUCCUAGAACACAGAAGGGUACCAGUAAUACACUAAAUUUUCAAGGUGUGUAGAGAAAUAAUAUGGAAUUAGCAGCUAUGACUCCAACAGACAGGAUUGUGUGAGCAGCUGAAAGGAGCAAAAAAGAACUCAGUGUAAGAGAAGGCACAUACAUAGUUAAGAAUACUAAAGUAUUUUUAAAAAUCAAGGAAGAAAUAAAUGUUACACAAUUUGCAUUGGAAUAAAUAGAUCUAUUUAGUCCUACAAAUCAGGAGUGGUGUAGAGACAUCCAAAUUUAAAGAAAAAAAAACACAAAACAGAAUGUUAAAAAAUGUAUGCAGAUUUAUGGAUAUUAUCAAUGAGAAGACAUAGCAUGUAACUUCUCCUAUAUCUCUACUGUCCAGCAUGUAUUGUUCCAAAUAUGACUCCCUAAAAUAUAUACACUUUGCAGAAGCUCUAGGCCCUCACCUCAAACCUUGCCAUUGGUUGCCGUAUUUCAAGGUCAAUAUAGUUUCCCUCACUUUACACAAUCAUUAUUCUUCAAUAGUGGACCAUAUCCUUCACCAGGUAUCCUAUUUCUGUUAUCUAGAGGUUAGCAGAAAAUGAAAUGAAGGAAUUUCCCUAAGCAGUUGGGAAGAACAAAUUGUAUGCAUGUAGGCAAAGAUUUUGAAGAUACAUUUGCAAGAGAUAUUUGUUUAACCAAAAUAUUUGGAAAGUAACAAAUAAAGACAUUUAAAUUUUCUAAAAAUGGACUUGCUCUUCUAGGAAAAGAAUACCCCUGGGGCAAAAAUAUAACUCUAGCUGUAUUUCUUCUUGUCACUCUUGAUUCAACUUGAUUAUAAAUACACCUGUCACUACCAGAACCAAAAAAAAAAAGAAAAAAAUCCCAAGCACAAAGCUUAUUUUAUUUGAAAAAAAUAAAAAAGAAACUUCAACACUAUGGGACACUGGCUCUUUUAGCAUGAAAUGACUUGAGCUUUUGUAGUGAUGAUACACAUACACACUCAUCAGUAAAACGAUGGUUUCAUAAAUAACACAAUUGAUGCAAAUCAUAAAAAUCAAUUACAAUUAUGAUUUCAUGACAAAAUAUAUUUAAUUAAGUUUGUUAUGAAAAAAAUAGAGAUAUGAAUCACUAACAAAAUUCCUCCAUUUUCAGUGGCUAUUCAUCAUUUAUCAUCUAGACUCACAUUUGUCUCCUUCCUGAUAGCAGUUAAGAAAAAAUUCUAACCACACAAUUUGUAUAUUGUUUUUCUCCGUAUUAUGUUAAGCAAAUGUUCACUGCAGUAAAAUGUUUUGGAAAUUAGCUUUGUCUUAUUUCCAGUUUAGUUCAGAGAAUUAAUUGGAAACCUGAUUUCUUUUACACAUAAACCUGACAAAAAAUGUAGCUUAGAGCAAAGGGUGAAUGUUUGCUUAACUCCUGCUUACUUCUCAAGUACAUGAAAACUUUAAUAGAAUAUGCCAGUAUUCACUGAGUUUUUAAAAAUAUUACCAUGUGUAAACAUAUAAUAUCCAACUUCAUCCAAAAAUAUGGUUGAGUUUAAGUACUUUGUUUUUCAGGCUUAUUUCAAGUAUAAUAAUUCUUUGAUUUUCAUUGUUCUGAUUUCUGGGUCUUCAAUUCAUUCGUCACUUUUCCUUUUUAAGUAAAAUAAGCUUUUUUUUUUUUUUUUUUUUUUUUUUGGAGUUGCAUUGGGAUUUUUCCCAGGAAAAAAUAUGGCUUUUAGUAAUGCUUUGCAAUUGGCUACGCAGAUAUAAAUUAAGAUAUGUUUAUUCUGAGUUCUUAUUGGAAUAAGUUUCAAAAUCAACGAGCUUAAGAAUGAAAACAAAACUUUUGAGAGUCUCACAAAAUAGCUUUCUGGUCAAUACACCUUACUUGAUUUUUAAGCUCGCAGAAUAAAGUAUAGAAACAAAUGGAGCUGAAGUUCCAUUUGCUAAUUCAGAGACUUUUGUGCUUCCGCAAAUUGGAGGGCAGCAAGCCAUCCUAUUCUCAUAGUAAUCGUUUUGGCUUUGAAAUUUACAUACAAUUUAAUAGCACAUUUUUAGCCAUUAUGGAUUGGCGCAAUAAAGAGAUAUCAAUGUAAUGCAAUGUGAUGCUUUAUGGGCCUCAUUCUAAUUCAGAAAGCUUGUUUAAAAGAACUAAGACUCUUCUGUUUAAUAAAAUAGCAACAAUCUAAUAUCUAGAUUGGUAGUCCUGCGGUGCCACUAGUGGGAGAUGAGAGUAUUAAGACAAGAGUAAGGACAAGGAAAGACUUAAAGGUUGCAUAUUGAAAAGUUUGGAAUUCCUAAUUUGGGAGCACUGAUUUCUUGGUGAAGAAGUAAGUAUGACUACGUUGCCAGUAAUUUUUUAAAAACAUAGACCCAGAAAUAGCAAAUCGAUUUCACCCUCAUACCUUAGUCUACAAGGCCUUGCUCUUGAGAAGGUUUUCCAUGAUAUUGCUUAAUUUCAUCUGCACAAGAUGAGACACAAACAUAAAAAUUCCCUGCUCAUUUUAAUACCAUAAAAGGCUGAGGUUAUUUCUCUGUCAUAAAAUUGUAAAUAGCAUUUUUUAAGUCAAAAUUACAUUUAAAACAGUGGAUUGUUCUACAAAUAUAUAUGUGUAUAUAUACAUAUGCUUCUGAAAUAAGGAUAUAUUAUAUGAGUUUUUAUUUGAUUUGUGGUCUUUAGUCAUAGGUAAUCAAAAAUAAAGAGAUUUGAAUGCAAAACUUUAUACAUUAAUGUACAUUUCUAAUGAUGGUACAAAUUGCCACUUUAUAAUAAAAAAGAAACAGGUGGGAAUAAUAAUCAAAGCACGUGUUCCUUCAGUACUUUGGUGAUUUUUAAUCCCCCUUGUGAUGCACAGGAAAUUAUUUUUUAGUUACAAAAAGUUAUCUUAGAAAUCUAUACUUCCCAAUACAGAUUUCAUGUUAAGUCAUAUCAAAUUGAGAAUUUGUGGUGAAAGAAUAGGAAAAGGAUGCUAGAUGCUGAUCUUUCUUUUUCAGGAUUUUUCCUGGAGCCCAAGUUAAAAAUUCAAUACUUAAAUCUAAGUUAAGUGAAAAUUAAUAAUGUUCAGAAUGAUGUAUUGAGCUUUAGUAACAGACGGAAGCAAAAAAAAAUAAGAAUAUUUAACAUUAUGAUAAUAGCCUUAAAAUAAUGUAAUAAAAAUUGCAUCAUUAAAUGUUCUAUUAGUUGGAAAGAAUGAGCUGAUGUUUCUUUGUCUUUGCUCCAAGUACAAUUUAAAGACAGUGACAUUCAUUUUACUUAAAAUUGUUCAAAAAGUCCAAAACAUACUCCCAUGGCUAGAAUUGGUAUUAGCUCCAAUACAAGGUUAAAUGUUACAAUCUUAAGAAAUUAUUGACACUGAAAUGUUUAGUAAACAUGUUGUAUGAGAAACUAAACAAAUUAAUGUUUCAUUUUUCCAUUAAAGCACAGAUUAUUCAAA